AGCGGCACUGGCCCAGCAGAGCAGGACACUAGAACACGGUAGCAGUGGCCCAUGGGAAGAGAUGAGGCCUCAAAAAAUGAAUGCAUCUGGAGACCUAGCCUCCUUCUCCUCUUUGUACCAACCCAACUCCGAAACCUCUGUAGGGGCCGACCUGCUGGAAAAGAAUCUUGCUGAGAUACAGAACCUGCGCCAGCGCCUGGAGGAGUCCAUCAGUCUCAAUGACCGCCUGAGGGAGAGGCUGCAGCAUGUGCUUAGCAAUGGUGACCAAGGAAAAGAUAAUCAGAGAGUCACUAGCUGUCAACUAGAAAGCUUGGUGUCUCUCUUCCUGUCUUUCCCACUUUCACCUGGGUACGGAAUAGGAGAGAAGAAAUUAAGUUUUUGUUUGGUACAAUCAAUGAAUCUCCUAAAUCCCUCCAGACUUCAUUGCAGCCCUGUCUCUCCCUCCCUAGGUACUGCACAGUCCACUGUAGCCCCUCAUUCAUAUACUCAGAGUCACUCUUCUGGCUGUGGCGAGGACAUCCUGUGACAUGAUGCCUAGAGAGUCUGGAAGAAUGUUCUCCAGAACUUUUCCAGCCCUAUCCAACAGAAUUCUUGGGUGGGAACUUGGAGGCAUUGGAUAUUAUCUUUAAAUGAAGAGAUCAAAUUAAUAAAUUAUUUUUAAAAUUAA